GAAGUCUCGCGAGCCCGGAGCGUGGCACGUGGGUUGGUAACUGUGGCGCUGCUCCGCGUCCACCACCACCCCUGUCCUCCUCAGGCCCCCUCCGCCUCCACCCCUGCCCUCCUCAGGCCCCCUCCGCCUCCACCCCUGCCCUACUCAGGCCCCCUCCGCCUCCACCCCUGCCCUCCUCAGGCCCCCUCCGCCUCCACCCCUGCCCUCCUCAGGCCCCCUCCGCCUCCACCCCUGCCCUCCUCAGGCCCCCUCCGCCUCCACCCCUGCCCUCCUCAGGCCCCCUGCGUCCCCGCCUCGUCCUCCUCAGGCCCCCUCCGCCUCCGGCUCCGUCCUCCUCAGGCCCCCUCCGCCUCCGGCUCCGUCCUCCUCUGGCCCCCUCCGCCCCCGGCCCCGGCCCCACGGCGGGAUGCGGGACAACACCAGCCCCAUCAGCGUGAUUCUGGUGAGCUCGGGGAGCAGGGGCAAUAAGCUGCUGUUCAGGUACCCCUUCCAGAGAAGCCAGGAGCACCCGGCGUCCCAGACAAGUAAGCCGCGUAGCAGAUACGCUGCCAGCAACACGGGCGACCAUGCUGAUGAGCAGGACGGCGAUUCCAGGUUUUCAGAUGUUAUUCUGGCAACAAUUUUGGCAACCAAGUCUGAAAUGUGUGGCCAAAAAUUUGAACUGAAGAUUGAUAAUGUGCGAUUUGUUGGGCACCCAACACUGCUACAGCAUGCUCUGGGGCAGGCCAACGCAGACCCGUCAGUGAUAAACUGUCUGCAUAACCUGUCCCGUCGUAUCGCCACCGUGCUGCAGCACGAGGAGCGCCGCUGCCAGUACCUCACCCGGGAGGCCAAGCUGAUCCUGGCGCUCCAGGAUGAGGUGUCCGCCAUGGCUGAUGGAAAUGAAGGUCCUCAGUCCCCAUUCCAUCACAUCCUGCCCAAGUGCAAGCUGGCCAGGGACCUCAAGGAAGCUUAUGACAGCCUGUGCACGUCGGGCGUAGUUCGGCUUCACAUCAACAGCUGGCUGGAGGUGAGCUUCUGCCUGCCCCACAAGAUCCACUAUGCGGCCUCCAGUCUGAUCCCCCCAGAGGCCAUCGAACGGAGCCUGAAAGCCAUCCGCCCCUACCAUGCCCUGCUGCUGCUCAGUGAUGAGAAGUCCUUGCUGGGUGAGCUUCCUAUUGACUGCUCCCCUGCCCUAGUGCGGGUGAUCAAGACCACAUCUGCUGUGAAGAACCUGCAGCAGCUAGCCCAAGAUGCGGACCUGGCCUUGCUGCAGGUUUUCCAGCUUGCAGCUCAUCUGGUGUACUGGGGCAAGGCCAUCAUCAUCUACCCGCUGUGUGAGAACAACGUCUACAUGCUGUCUCCCAAUGCCAGCGUAUGUCUGUACUCCCCGCUGGCCGAGCAGUUCUCCCACCAGUUCCCAUCUCAUGACCUGCCGUCCGUUCUUGCCAAGUUCUCCUUGCCGGUCUCCUUGUCAGAAUUUAGGAAUCCCCUGGCCCCCGCUGUGCAGGAGACCCAGCUCAUCCAGAUGGUGGUGUGGAUGCUGCAGCGCCGGCUUCUCAUCCAGCUGCACACCUAUGUCUGCCUGAUGGCCUCACCCAGCGAGGAGGAGCCCCGUCCGCGAGAGGACGACGUCCCCUUCACUGCCCGGGUCGGCGGUCGCAGCCUCAGCACGCCCAACGCCCUCAGCUUUGGCUCCCCAACCAGCAGCGAUGACAUGACCCUCACCAGCCCCAGCAUGGACAACUCCAGCGCAGAGCUACUUCCCAGCGGGGACUCGCCACUGAACCAGAGGAUGACGGAGAACCUGCUGGCCAGCCUGUCGGAGCAUGAACGCGCAGCCAUCCUCAGUGUACCCGCAGCCCAGAACCCUGAGGACCUCCGCAUGUUUGCCAGGCUCCUUCACUACUUCCGCGGCCGCCACCACCUGGAGGAGAUUAUGUACAACGAGAACACGCGGCGCUCCCAGCUGCUCAUGCUGUUUGACAAGUUCCGCAGCGUGCUGGUGGUGACCACCCACGAGGACCCUGUCAUUGCCGUCUUCCAGGCUCUGCUCCCCUGAGCCCAGGCGGAGGGCGGAAGGCUGCUGGGGUGCGCAGGUGGGCGCUCGCGUCUCCCCACCCCAGGGCUCCCCCCGUGCUGAGGCUGAGCCCUCUUGGCCCUGAGGCCUGGCAUUGGGUGGAUGCGGGCUGGCCGUGGCCCAGUGAAGCCUGCAGAGCCCCGCUGUCCUUGCCCCUGGUGGUUCCGCUGUGGGGCUGCUGCCCUCUGUGUUCCUACGCUUCCCUCCAGUCCUUGCCGCACGCGUAGGCAUCUCCACGCUGGAGGGGGGCCUGCCAGGACUCCUGUCUCUGGGUGAGGCCGCAUCCUUCAAGGCCCAUGUGGGCUGUGCGUUUCUCAGACCCUCCUUCUGUCCCUACACCUGCUCCUUGGACCCCCCAGUCUGUGGCCACCCUGAAGAAUGUGCAGAAACACUUGUGUGGCCUGUCCCUGUCUCUCUGACAGCCUUCUAUUUGUGAAGUGCCCUGUGGCCCCCUCCCCAGCACCUCUGUCUGCCAUGCGCUUCUUCCUCCCAGGCUACCCUGAGCCUUUCCUGGCCCAGUCCUCACCACAGUCCACAGAAGCCGCAAACAGGCUCAUAGCCAAGCUGUGACCUGGUCCUGACCAUCUGGGGCACGAGGGCCUGGGCUGGCCCUGCUAGGCUGGAGAAGCCCUGUCACCUGUGCACAUCUUGCUGGUGGAGGCAUGGCCCACUGUGCAGGACCCCACCCUCGGGGGCUUUCGGCUCCCACACUGAUGAUUCUCCCCAGCAUCCACACCGGGCCUGGCGCUACGUACUCAGGCCCCCAGCUCUCGUGUCCUGGAGGAAGAGCUAGCUCCAGACAUGGGUUGAUCACCUAGAGGAGCUCUGGCUAAGGCACAGUUUUCUAGAAAUAAAACAUUUAUUCGGUUUUUAAACAAUUAAAAAAUCUUGUCUGGGCAGGCCCUUUGCUCAGGCCUGUGUGUCCUGCUCAGCCACUCUGUCGACCACACUGACCCAGGGGCUGCCCCGGACAUAGAAGCGGAGGGGUUUCCGGGCCCACUCCCCUGCAUGGCCGACGCCCACCCGGGCUGCUGCCACUACAGCCGGCUCACUGGGCUCCAGGGGACCACGCUCCAGCCAUACAGCUUCAUCCUGUGCCAGGUCCCUCUGGUCAAAGCUCUUGUUGAUGGCCAGGGCCUGGCACAGCUUGGAGGGGCCACUGCAGAGCUCGCGGUCCUUGAGGACACGGCUGGCGGUGCCUUUCCGGAGGGUGCUGCGAAGCUGACGCAUGGUCUCCAGACCUUCCAGGGGCUCCAGUGCUCGCAGCAAGACGCAAGCCCCGUCCCCUGUGGGACGGACAG